GGCAACACGCUGGGUUUGCUUUACAACGCUUGGGAAGCUUUGUUGUUUGCAAUAAAUUUUAAUACUUGUCUGUUUCGGUCUGCACUGCCUUUAUGAGCUGUAACACUCACAGGGUAGGUUUGCAGCUUCACUCCUGAAGCCAGUAAGACAACGAACCCACUGGGAGAAACAAACAACUCCAGACGCGCCGACUUAAGAGCUGUAAUACUCGCUGUGACGGUCUGCAGCUUCACUCCUGAGCCAGCGAGACCACGAACCCACCAGAAGGAAGAAACUCCGAACACAUCUGAACAUCAGAAGGAACAGACUCCGGACACGCCGCCUUUAAGAACUGUAACACUCACCGCGAGGGUGGGCGGUUUCAUUCCUGAAGUCAGUGAGACCAAGAACCAACCAAUUCCGGACACACUUGGACUCGACAGACUCUAAGGCUCUACAGAGAGCGGCUGCAGAGCUCACCCGGCUGGCAGGAGCCACCGAGGCCGGACACGUGGGCGACUUAUUGACCAAGUGGGGAGGAAGCAGCCCCGCACUGCUCUCCCGACUGCGGACCACCGUUGGGCUCCUGCGCAUCCUAAGCCCCACCGCCUCACCUCCAGUCCCCACAGCGUUCGCGCUCCCAGCCGGGGUCCAGCCGGCCGGUGAGCGCCUGGGGACCGCAGAGGUGAGAGUCGCGCCCGGGAGUCCGCCGCCUGCGCCAGGAUGGAGUUCGUGAAAUGCCUUGGCCACCCCGAAGAGUUCUACAACCUGGUGCGCUUCCGGAUCGGGGGCAAGCGGAAGGUGAUGCCCAAGAUGGACCAGGACUCGCUCAGCAGCAGCCUGAAAACUUGCUACAAGUAUCUCAAUCAGACCAGUCGCAGUUUCGCAGCUGUUAUCCAGGCGCUGGAUGGGGAAAUGCGCAACGCAGUGUGCAUAUUUUAUCUGGUUCUCCGAGCUCUGGACACACUGGAAGAUGACAUGACCAUCAGUGUGGAAAAGAAGGUCCCGCUGUUACACAACUUUCACUCUUUCCUUUACCAACCAGACUGGCGGUUCAUGGAGAGCAAGGAGAAGGAUCGCCAGGUGCUGGAGGACUUCCCAACGAUCUCCCUUGAGUUUAGAAAUCUGGCUGAGAAAUACCAAACAGUGAUUGCCGACAUUUGCCGGAGAAUGGGCAUUGGGAUGGCAGAGUUUUUGGAUAAGCAUGUGACCUCUGAACAGGAGUGGGACAAGUACUGCCACUAUGUUGCUGGGCUGGUCGGAAUUGGCCUUUCCCGUCUUUUCUCAGCCUCAGAGUUUGAAGACCCCUUAGUUGGUGAAGAUACAGAACGUGCCAACUCUAUGGGCCUGUUUUUGCAGAAAACAAACAUCAUCCGUGACUAUCUGGAAGACCAGCAAGGAGGAAGAGAGUUCUGGCCUCAAGAGGUUUGGAGCAGGUAUGUUAAGAAGUUAGGGGAUUUUGCUAAGCCGGAGAAUAUUGACUUGGCCGUGCAGUGCCUGAAUGAACUUAUAACCAAUGCACUGCACCACAUCCCAGAUGUCAUCACCUACCUUUCGAGACUCAGAAACCAGAGUGUGUUUAACUUCUGUGCUAUUCCACAGGUGAUGGCCAUUGCCACUUUGGCUGCCUGUUAUAAUAACCAGCAGGUGUUCAAAGGGGCAGUGAAGAUUCGGAAAGGGCAAGCAGUGACCCUGAUGAUGGAUGCCACCAAUAUGCCAGCUGUCAAAGCCAUCAUAUAUCAGUAUAUGGAAGAGAUUUAUCAUAGAAUCCCCGACUCAGACCCAUCUUCUAGCAAAACAAGGCAGAUCAUCUCCACCAUCCGGACGCAGAAUCUUCCCAACUGUCAGCUGAUUUCCCGAAGCCACUACUCCCCCAUCUACCUGUCGUUUGUCAUGCUUUUGGCUGCCCUGAGCUGGCAGUACCUGACCACUCUCUCCCAGGUAACAGAAGACUAUGUUCAGACUGGAGAACACUGAUCCCAAAUUUGUCCAUAGCUGAAGUCCACCAUAAAGUGGAUUUACUUUUUUUCUUUAAGGAUGGAUGUUGUGUUCUCUUUAUUUUUUUCCUACUACUUUAAUCCCUAAAAGAACGCUGUGUGGCUGGGACCUUUAGGAAAGUGAAAUGCAGGUGAGAAGAACCUAAACAUGAAAGGAAAGGGUGCCUCAUCCCAGCAACCUGUCCUUGUGGGUGAUGAUCACUGUGCUGCUUGUGGCUCAUGGCAGAGCAUUCAGUGCCACGGUUUAGGUGAAGUCGCUGCAUAUGUGACUGUCAUGAGAUCCUACUUAGUAUGAUCCUGGCUAGAAUGAUAAUUAAAAGUAUUUAAUUUGAAGCACCAUUUGAAUGUUCGUAAUAGUAGAAAAUGAUGUGAAUUUUCUUUCUGUUCGGCUCCUAUUUUUCUCAUCAUUUUGUUUUCUUUAAUUGGGUUGAAUGGAGUAGAUAGAAAUAUUUAUGGUUUAGGUAACAGUUAGAUGUUUCCUAAGAAUGCAAACUGCCUUUUCCACACAAAGGCUGGGAAUAAAAUUCUGGGUAUUCUCGUAUUCUCAUUUAAAGGAGUUUAGCUUUCAGAGAGAAACAGCAGGAUUGCUUUUGACCUUUUAGAAGAUUGGUCUCCAGUAAAGGUGGACAUUUUUGAGAUUUUUAUAAUAAAGAAUUUAAUUGCUCUGCA